CUCUCGGCCUUAGCGCCAUUUUUUUGGGUGAGUGUUUUUUGGUUCCUGCGUUGGGAUUCCGUGUACAAUCCAUAGACAUCUGACCUCGGCACUUAGCAUCAUCACAGCAAACUAACUGUAGCCUUUCUCUCUUUCCCUGUAGAAACCUCUGCGCCAUGAGAGCCAAGUGGAGGAAGAAGCGAAUGCGCAGGCUGAAGCGCAAAAGAAGAAAGAUGAGGCAGAGGUCCAAGUAAACCGCUAGCUUGUUGCACCGUGGAGGCCACAGGAGCAGAAACAUGGAAUGCCAGACGCUGGGGAUGCUGGUACAAGUUGUGGGACUGCAUGCUACUGUCUAGAGCUUGUCUCAAUGGAUCUAGAACUUCAUCGCCCUCUGAUCGCCGAUCACCUCUGAGACCCACCUUGCUCAUAAACAAAAUGCCCAUGUUGGUCCUCUGCCCUGGACCUGUGACAUUCUGGACUAUUUCUGUGUUUAUUUGUGGCCGAGUGUAACAACCAUAUAAUAAAUCACCUCUUCCGCUGUUUUAGCUGAAGAAUUAAAUCAUCUUGUCUAUUAUGUUUUUUAUGGUUCCAUCGGGUGGGGGUUUUCUGUCAUUAGAGUUUGCCCUGUCACUACCUGUGCUAUGGAGGGUAUCAAAGCUAUAAAGGCAACAGCCCGGGUUACGUGGUGUGGUUUGCA